CGGGGAAAAUAUUGAGAGAGACAGAAAGAAAAGGAGAAACUUAUCUGAGGUUGGAAAUAAAGAGAAGGUGACAUUGGAGCGGAUAGAAAGGAAGAAACGGCGUGGGAUCUGGGAAUGAGGCAGUGGGUGGAGAGAGAAUGGGGAGACGACAGAGGAUGAAGGGCAGCUGAGUGUGUCUGCGGGAGAAGGACCAAAGCAAUCUGGGCGGAGCAGGUGGCAGAGGCAGCCGCGGAGGAGGCCCAGGGAACUGACGGGGAUGCUCAGCCAGGCCCAGAGGAUGCGCCCUGGCAGUCCCGGAAAACACCAGGAAAACAAGCAGGAACCGUAGCUAGGACUGGGGUGGCCAGGCCCAGGAAAUCCAUGAAGGGCACAGACAGCGGGUCCUGCUGCCGCCGCCGAUGCGACUUUGGCUGCUGCUGUCGCGCGUCCCGCCGGGCUCACUACACGCCUUACCGGUCCGGGGACGCGACGCGAACCCCUCAGUCCCCACGGCAGACCCCGAGCCGGGAAAGACGGCGCCCGGAGCCAGCCGGGAGCUGGGCAGCAGCGGCCGAGGAGGAAGAAGCAGCUGCGGCGGCCACACCCUGGAUGAGAGAUUAUUUUGCAGAGGAUGAUGGGGAGAUGGUACCCAGAACGAGUCACACAGCAGCUUUUCUUAGUGACACUAAAGAUCGAGGCCCUCCAGUGCAGUCACAGAUCUGGAGAAGUGGUGAAAAGGUCCCGUUUGUGCAGACAUAUUCCUUGAGAGCAUUUGAGAAACCCCCUCAGGUACAGACCCAGGCUCUUCGAGACUUUGAGAAGACAUGGAGAGUUUGCAUGGUAAUCAAGAGGCUUUUGAAGACUAAACCUCCGAACAGCUGUGUGGUGCUGGUGGGGGAAGCAAGGAUGCUAACACCCCAACCCCCUCCUUUUUUUGUUUUUUUUUUUUCACCUUUUGGAUCUGCUGUGAUGCAGAAAGGGCAAGCAGAGCUGCAGAGCUCCUCAAAACUGUGUGGGGUGCUCUCCAAAGGCCAGCCAGCCUGCAUGUUCCUUUUCAUUGAGAGAUGACUGGAAAUAUAGAAAUGAGGGGUGUCACCUCCAUUGAAAGAAUGGGUGGCAGAUAUAAGGCCCAAAGUCCUUUUCUUUUAGAGUUUAGAUCUAAUAUGACAGAUUAGUCCUUAUUUCUCGAUGCUGGGAAACACUGACAGAAACCAAGCUAAGACGCAGGGAAAAGGCCAAUAAGAGAUAGUUUAAAUCUCUCUCUGCUAUGUGUCAAAUAAAAAGUAAAUAAAGAGGCUACAACCCACUUCAGGCUUGAUCAGAAAGUCAUUGCCGGUAAAUCAUGCAGUGUUGUGUCACACGUUUGUUCAUUUUCAUAUCCGUUCAUCCAUCCUGUGGACUCUGAAUGACAGCACCUAAAAUACAAAACGCCUCCAUGAAAGGGUUUAAAAAUUAGAGAAAACAUUGGUUAGAAAAAAUACAGGAGAGAUAGGAACACAUUCCUAUGCCCUACCCUAAAAAUGGUAAAAUACUAAAUAACAUGGUAUUUUCUGUAAAGUUUAAAAUAUGCAUUUGGUAGCCUUGGGAUAUAGGAUAGGUAGCAGUACUCAGAGAGAGGAGGGGACAUGCUAAAUGUUUUUUGCCAAAGUAGGGUCGACUCCUCCAGGGCUUAAAGACAAAGGGAGACAGGCCUGGAAGAAGCAGCCAGGAAUCCCUUCUUAUUUCAUUUAUCCAUGCAACAAACACAUGAUCACAUUAAAUGAGAUACUUUAGUUCCUGCCCUUAGAUAGUUAUAGUCUAUUUGGAAGUACAGACAUUGCAUUAAAUACAAUAUAGCAUGGCAAGUGCUUUCAUAGAGAUAAGGACAGUACACUCUGAGAUCUUGAGAGAAAAUGUCUACUUUUAUUAAAGGAGUAGGGAAAGGCCUCUUACCAGAGGACAUUUCUCCUGGGGGCUUCACGUUGAGCAAGGUCUCCAAAGCUGAGUUAGAUUUUACUAGUCAGGGAAGUAGAGUAUAAUAUUCCAGACAGAGGGGAGAUUUGGGGGAAGGAAGAGAGAUAUGUUCAAAUAAGAGACUGGACUAUAGAGAGGUAAGAAAAAGAGAGUUAGAACAGGAGAGAAGUAAUACUAAAAGUACUCAAUCUGUCAAAAGUAAUUAUAAUUGUUCAGUAAUGCAGUUACCUCUAAAAUGUUUGCUGAUGUAGGAAAUUCUAGAGAAAAAAGGCUCUUUGAUUACAGGGAAAGAGAUAACAGACUAAAAAUGCAAAUACUGGCACAUUAUGGAACCAAAACAUAAUUAGUCAAUUAACAAGCGAAAGUGACAAUUAUCAUUUAUGUUGGUGUAGAAAAAAGGGACAAAGAAAGCAACAUUUCCAACAUACAACAGUGUUUCUUUUCUUUCAUUCUCCACCCACAACCAACAGCAUGGUUGUAUGUGUAUACAAACUCCAAUUGUAUGUUUGUCAGGUUGAGGUCAAUAGGUAUUACACUCCAUGAUGAAAGGAGGGCAUUGCUUAGCAUAUAUGCUUCAUUUGUAUUUUUGAAUGAGUGAGUGAUUUAAUUAAUUUCCCAACCUUACCAACUUCGUUAUGUAGGCGCUUUUCCCCACUCAGAGAAUCCACUGAUGAAGGGAUUCUCUGUGGGUUUAGUGUAUUGAGCAGUGGGUUUAGUGUAUUGAGCAGUGGGUUAAGUGUAUCUCAUAAGUUGUUUUAUUUUGUCUUUAUAAGACACGGAACAAGCAUCACUCUCCCCAUUUUUUAAGUGAGGGAACCAGGACUCACGGAAAUUGUGACUUUUUCAGGGCCAUAAGUUUAUGUACCAUGAUCAUAAAUCUGAACACAUUAUUGGAUCAGAAAUAAAUUUUACCUACAAAUGGUCACAAUGAUGUGUUGAGAAAAAUCCCUUGCCCUAUGCUUUCUCGCUGAUCACAGCACCCAGCUGCAGCAUCUCUGGAAUGAGCAAGACUUCAGCAGCACAUACAUAAUACUGGCUAGCAUUUGAUGAUCACUUUCUAUGUGGCAGAUAUUGCUCUAAGUAUGUGACAGCAUGAUCUCAUUUACAACAACCUUGUGAAAAGGCAUGUUCACCAGUUAGAAUGGCGAUCAUUAAAAAUCAGGAAACAACAGGUGCUGGAGAGGAUGUGGAGACAUAGGAACGCUUUUACACUGCUGGUGGGAGUGUAAAUUAGUUCAACCAUUGUAAAAGACAGUGUGACAAUUCUUCAAGGAUCUAGAACUAGAAAUGCCAUUUGACCCAGCAAUCCCAUUACUGGGUAUAUACCCAAAGGAUUAUAAAUCAUUCUACUAUAAAGACACAUGCACACGUAUGUUUAUUGCAGCACUAUUAACAAUGGCAAAGACUUGGAACCAACCCAAAUGCCCAUUAAUGUUAGAAUGGAUAAAGAAAAUGUGGCACAUAUACGCCAUGGAAUACUAUGCAGCCAUAAAAAAAGAAUGAGUUCAUGUCCUUUGCAGGGACGUGGAUGAAGCUGGAAACCAUCAUUCUCAGCAAACUAACACAGGAACAGAAAACCAAACACCCUAUGUUCUCACACAUAAAUGGGAGUUGACUAAUGAGAACACAUGGACACAGGGAGGGGAUCAUCACGCACAGGGGCCUGUCAGGGGCUGUGGGGCAAGGUGAGGGAUAAUAUUAGGAGAAAUACCUAAUAUAGAUGACGGGUUGAUGGGUGUGGCAAACCAACAUGGCACACGUAUACUGUGCAACAAACCUGCACGUUCUGCACAUGUAUCCCAGAACUUCAAAUAUAAUAAAAAAAAGAAAAGCCAUGAUUAUUAUUCCAGUUUACAAAUGAUGAACUAAUGGCAAAAAGAAUAACAAAGGAACUUGUCCAAUAACUCAUGAUUGAGCCUGAAAACACCUGAUGUCUUUGUGACCUAAAGAUAGUGGGCAUGUCCUAUGUUGGGGAACUCAGCUGGUGAAAGUUUGGUGCUAAUGAAGGUGUUGGCUUAUUUGGAAAUGGAAUCACUAGUUCCUCCUAUUUAGAUUGAUGCAGAUUGAAAUCCUACCAGAUUCCUGCCUCUCUAGGUAAACUGUAAAUCCACUUUUGUCUUCCAGUAUUCUCUAUUACAUGAUUUUUACUCUAUUAAUUCUGAACUGCUUGCAAUUCAAAGCUGUUUCAUACUUUCAUUUAUUUGUACCUGCUGUUCCCUCUGCCUUGAAAACCUUUUCUCUCCUAUUGUUUAUUUGGUUAAAGUUUACUCAUCCUUCAAGAUUCAGCUCAGGUGCCUUUUUAAAUUUAUUUAUUUUUUAAUUUUAGGAUGCCUUCUCUUACUCUCUAAUCCCAGAAUAUAUACCAAGACUCUAAGCUCCUUGAGGGCAGAAAACACCUCUUGCCCAUUCUUUUCUAGUCUCUAGAAUAUAGCAUAAUGUAGUACAUAGUAAGUGCUCAGUAAAUAUUCAUCAACUAAACUAGCUGAAAAGUAUUAAAAAUUAGAUAUCCUAUUGGAUUUGUAUCUCUUCUGCCUCUACCUGGUAUUCACAAUAAGUUGAAUAGUUUUAAGGAGGGUAUUGGUGUGUUAGUUGAUUGGGUAGGAUGGGAAACUAGGAAGUCAAGAAAUGUACAUUUCUUUUCCACUUUAUUUUUUUAUUGUUCAUUUUUUUUGAGAAGGAGUCUUGCUGUGUCACCCAGGCUGGAGUGCAGUGGUGCAAUCUCAGCUCACUGCAGCCUCUGCCUCCUGGAUUCAAGCAGUUCUCCUGCCUGAGUAGCUGGGACUACAGGCUCCCGCCACCACACCCGGCUAAUGUUUUGCAUUUUUAGUAGAGAUGGAGUUCCGCUAUGUUGGUCAGGCUGGUCUCCAAAUCCUGGCCUCAAGUGGUCCACCCUCCUUGGCCUCCCAAAGUGCUGGAAUUUCAGGCGCGAACUACGCGCCUGGCCUCUUUUCCACUUUAAAUGGAAUGAUAAAACUAAAAAUGAAAAGGACGGGAGAGAAAGAGUCUUUUUGAAAUAAUAUUUGACAGGAUUUAUUAAGAAGAUCACAAUAGUAGCUAAUAACAAUAAAUACUAUUUGAGUGCUCAUUAUGCACCAGGUACUUUUCUAGAUAUUUGACAUAUUUAAUUUAGUGUAUUUUCAGUUCAUUUUCCUAACUUAUGAGAUAGAUAUUAUUUUUACAACCAUUAUACUAGUGAAGAGAUCAAGGUUCAAAUAACUUGCCCAAAGUUAUAUAAGAAUAAAGUAACGGAACCACUGUAACUCCAAUGAUUCCAAAGCUCUUGGGGAAAUGAAAGGACUCUCAGAGAAGGAGAGCAUUACAUUGGUGGAAUGCCUGCAUUUGGGUUUUUUACAUAGAAUCAACAUGGCAGACGGUACAGAAAAGCCACGGAAGGGUGGGAGUCUUUGGCUAUAAAAUCAAGAGGGGGCCUCCACUGCCCUGUCCUGUUUACACAUUUUUCUAAUAAUGUUGUCUUUAACAAGAAAAUAUCAUCAAAACCAGCUGUAGUGUAUGCCUAACUGUACUCUGCAGCUUUCCUUGGCAGUCUGAAUCUAACCGCAGUGAGUCAGCCUGUUCAGGUCCCACCCAUCCUGGUGAACUUUUCCACUUGAAUCUUGAAGUCUUUGGGGAGAAAAAAGAAAAAAAAAAGUGCUAAAAGCAGAAGGCUUUUUCAUUUUGGGGAGUUUCUGGAGCUCUGAGUUAUCACAGUCUGGGUAACCUGUGCUAAUUUAGGUUAAUUGGGGUCCUGUCACUGCCCUCUUUAUGUUCCACAAUUUUGGUGCUUCUCGAGUGUUUCUCUCUAAUUACAGCCUUGGAAAAUGAAUACUACUAGUGAAGUGCAUUUUUAUUUAAAAAAAAUGCAUUCAUUCUUCCAAACCACAGUGUCCCAAACAUACUGGUUUUGUUUUCACUGGUAUCUUAAGACAUUCAAAAAGUUACUAGGAGGCAGGGGGUAAAUAUUAAACUUUCAGCAAUCACAAGUGCAGUUUGUUUUCCCUUUUCAAUCUCAUGUUUAAAAAGGGAAACAGAAGGCUUCCACACACAGGCAUUCCACAGACUUUCCAUGCAAAGUUUUCUUUCCUAAGCAACAUUACCAAAGAUAUGAAUCAAAUCAAUUACUUUUUUUCUUAUAGAACUACAGAGUAAAAGGAAUGCUUCUGAGUGCUGUAGAAUAUACAAAGAUGGACAUGAGAUUCCAUUCUCAAAGAAUGUACAAUCUGAUUGGGGCAUAAAAAAAUUUAAAUUAUACAAGAUUUAAUUUAAAUAACAUCUAAGGCAAUAUUGAAAGAGAUAUUUCAAGAUGGGAGUACUUGCCAAACUAAUGUAUGUUUUUAAAACUUAAAUAUGGCGAGGUGUGGUGAUCAUGCCUAUAAUUGCAGCACUUUGGGAGGCUGAGGUGAGCGAAUACCUGAGGUCAGGAGUUCGAGACUAGCCUGGCUAACAUGGUGAAACCCCAUCUCCAUUAAAAAUACAAAAAUUAGCUAGGCAUGGUGGCACAUGCCUGUAAUCCCAGUUACUCAGGAGGCUGAGGGAGGAGAAGCGCUUGAACCCAGAGGGCAGAGGUUGCAGUAAGCCGAGAUCGAGCCACUGCACUCCAGCCUGGGCGACAAAGUGAGACUCUGUCUCAAAUAAAUAAAUAAAUCUUAAAUACUGGGAUAGAACAUUUUUUCUAAUUUGUGCACGCGCGUGUGCGUGUGUAAACUUUUCAAAGUUGUAAAUAUUAGCUUACAUUUGGUCAUGCAAUUAAUAAAGAAACUUUAUCAAAAAGAAUGAAAUUACAAAAGUUGGACAACCCUGAACAUUCUGAAAGGUAUGAUUACCAACACAGAAAAGAGAGCAACCACUUUCACAGAGAAUGUAGCACUUGAAUUAGAAUAAUUCUUUUCGUAAUUUUAAAUUAUCUCCUUUCUGUCUCCUCAUUAAAACUUGUUUUCUUCUCUUCUCCCGUUGUUCGAAGAGAAGCCCUAUCUUUCUUUCUGUGGACUUUGCAAAGUUUCCAUUCUAAUGAUAAUUUCCAUUCCAAUACUAAAUUUAAAAAAUAGCAACAAAGAUCAUGAUACCAAUUAAUAUUUGUAAGUGCUUACAGUGUGCCAAGUUCUGAGAAUGCACUUGACCUUAUUAUCUUAUUCAGUUCUCCUAAUAGUCUUUUGAGGUUGGUACAACCAUUGUCUUUGUUUGUAGAGAGACACUGAAGCUAGGAAAACACUAGUAAUUGAUGGCAAGUGCUGGAGCUGGGAUUUGGACAUAAGUGUACUGGUUCUAGUGCCUAAACUCUUAGCCACAAUUUUAUUAUGCUUACUGAUAGCUGACCCCCUUAUUCAUUUGUUUGUUAAUCCACUCAUCCAUUUAUGAGUGCAUCGUGUGUGCCAGGCCAUGUUCUAGCUGUUAGUUGCACAAUGAUCAAGAAUGAAUGUAUGAAAAUAUGUAUUUUCGGCCGGGCGUGGCGGCUCACGCCUGUAAUUCCAGCACUUUAGGA